GCGGGAGAGGAGGCCAUGGGCGCGCGCGGGGCGCUGCUGCUGGCGCUGCUGCUGGCUCGGGCUGGACUCGGGAAGCCGGAGUCGCAGGAGGAGGAGCUGUUGUCAGAGGCCUGCGGCCACCGGGAAAUUCACGCGCUGGUGGCGGGCGGAGUGGAGUCCGCGCGCGGGCGCUGGCCAUGGCAGGCCAGCCUGCGCCUGAGGAGACGCCACCGAUGUGGAGGGAGCCUGCUCAGCCGCCGCUGGGUGCUCUCGGCUGCGCACUGCUUCCAAAAGCACUACUAUCCCUCCGAGUGGACGGUCCAGCUGGGCGAGCUGACUUCCAGGCCAACUCCUUGGAACCUGCGGGCCUACAGCAGUCGUUACAAAGUGCAGGACAUCAUUGUGAACCCUGACGCACUUGGGGUUUUACGCAAUGACAUUGCCCUGCUGAGACUGGCCUCUUCUGUCACCUACAAUGCGUACAUCCAGCCCAUUUGCAUCGAGUCUUCCACCUUCAACUUCGUGCACCGGCCGGACUGCUGGGUGACCGGCUGGGGGUUAAUCAGCCCCAGUGGCAGUGAGGCUGGGGAUAGACCGGGUGGGGUGAUGGGGGUGCGGGGUGAGCAUUACCCUCUACCCCUGUUCCCGCUACACAAGCACAGCAGCCCCCUCCUUGGUCUGGGGCUGCAACCUGCGCCCCUCCUGCUCUCAUUCUCUCCUCACUUGCUUUUCUGCUCUCACUGCCACCUGUCAGGGCAGGGACCAAACACCCAGUUCUUCCCCCUUCCAGGGACUGUGGGGGCCAGCAGGACAGUGUGAGAGGGAGGCCAGCUUGGCCUGGGCCUGAAGGAGUGAGGGGGAGUUCGGGAGGACCUGGUGACAGAAGCCUCAGGCAAUGAUUUUUAAAAAUUGAGGCAACUCACAAACCAUAAAAUUUUCAAGUGUUCAGUGUUGAAGGACACAAUUCAGUGAUUUGUAGCCUACAGUCAUGUGUCACUUAAUGACCGGGAUAUGUUCUGAGAUAUGCAUCAUGAGGCACUUUCAUCAUUGUGUCAACAUCAUGGAGUGUAGUUACACAAACCCAGAUGGCAGAGCCUGCUACACACCCAGACUGUGUGGUCUAGCCCAUUGCUCCUGGGCCACAAACCUGUGCAGCUUGUUACUGCACUAAAUACCAGAGCAGUUGUAACACACUGGUAAGUACUUAUGUACUUAAACAUAUCUAAACAGAGAAGAGGCACAGUAAAGAUAUGGCAUAAAAGAUAAAAACCAGGCCAGGCGCAUGAGCCUAUAAUCCCAGCACUUUGGGAGGCC